GAAAAGUGCAGCCGGUUUGAAAUGCAAGAUGGCGGCGGCGUGGCGCUGAGAGGCGCGGCGGCCCCUGCAGGAGAAGACAGACUGCUGCUUUGGACCUGUUGGUAAUGAUGGCCUGAGCUAAACAUCUAACUAGAAGGGAUACCCUUCCAUUUCAAAGAACAGAAUGCUAAGGAAGCUGUGGCAAUGGUUUUAUGAAGAAACAGAAAGCAGUGAUGAUGUUGAAGUGCUGACUCUCAAGAAAUUCAAAGGAGACCUGGCCUACAGACGACAAGAGUAUCAGAAAGCACUGCAGGAGUAUUCCAGUAUCUCUGAAAAAUUGUCAUCAACCAAUUUUGCCAUGAAAAGGGAUGUCCAGGAAGGUCAGGCUCGGUGUCUGGCUCACCUGGGUAGGCAUAUGGAGGCGCUGGAGAUUGCUGCAAACUUGGAAAAUAAAGCAACCAACACAGACCAUUUAACCACGGUACUCUACCUCCAGCUUGCUAUUUGUUCAAGUUUGCAGAACUUGGAGAAAACAAUUUUCUGCCUGCAGAAACUGAUUUCUUUGCAUCCUUUUAAUCCUUGGAACUGGGGCAAAUUGGCAGAGGCUUACCUGAAUCUGGGGCCAGCUCUUUCAGCAGCACUUGCGUCAUCUCAGAAACAGCACAGUUUCACCUCAAGUGACAAAACUAUCAAAUCCUUCUUUCCACACUCAGGAAAAGACUGUCUUUUGUGUUUUCCUGAAACCUUGCCUGAGAGCUCUUUAUUUUCUGUGGAAGCGAAUAGCAGUAAUAGCCAGAAAAAUGAGAAAGCUCUGACAAAUAUCCAAAACUGUAUGGCAGAAAAGAGAGAAACAGUGUUGAUAGAGACUCAGCUGAAAGCAUGUGCCUCUUUUAUACGAACCAGGCUUCUGCUUCAGUUUACCCAACCUCAGCAAACAUCGUUUGCUUUGGAGAGGAACUUAAGGACUCAGCAGGAAAUUGAAGAUAAAAUGAAAGGGUUCAGCUUCAAAGAAGACACUUUGCUGUUGAUAGCUGAGGUGAGUGUAUCCCUCGGGUUUAUGUGAAACGAAGCAUCAUAGAUAUUUUCCCUGGCUCUGAUAGCAUUUUUUAUAAAGCAGGGCCAAAUUUAAUCUACUGAAGGACUUGUCUCCCUCCUCUGUGUGCCUUUUGAUCACUCAGCAAUCACCAAGGCGGCCUCUUGAUCGGCAUUCCCCUGCAGCGUGCGGGACCGCAGGGGCUGUGUUUCAUGUACUUGUCAGUGCUUGUUAGCACCUGCCUGCCUGAACAUCAUCAAUGCCCAAUAAUUGUUUGUUUCAGUGCUGAAUAAAUGAAUGAAUGAAUGCUUA